AGCUGGCCUGCCCUAUGGCCGAGAGAUGGCUGCUGCCUCCGAGCCCGUGGAUUCGGGUGCACUCUGGGGACUCGAGCGCCCGGAGCCCCCUCCCACCCGCUUCCAUCGGGUGCACGGUGCCAACAUCCGCGUGGACCCCUCUGGGACGCGGGCCACACGCGUGGAGAGCUUCGCCCACGGCGUGUGCUUCAGCCGCGAGCCGCUGGCCCCGGGCCAGGUCUUCCUGGUCGAGAUCGAGGAGAAAGAGCUGGGCUGGUGCGGACAUCUGCGUCUCGGUCUGACCGCGCUGGACCCCGCCAGUCUGGCCCCCGUUCCCGAGUUUUCUCUGCCCGAUCUGGUCAACCUGGGCCACACCUGGGUCUUCGCCAUCACGCGCCACCACAACCGCGUGCCCCGGGAGGGCCGCCCGGAGGCGGAGGCAGCGGCCCCCAGCCGACCUCCAACCCUCCUCGUGGAACCAUAUCUGCGCAUUGAGCAGUUUCGCAUUCCCCGGGACCGCCUGGUGGGCCGCAGCCGGCCAGGGCUCUACAGCCAUCUCUUGGACCAGCUCUAUGAGCUGAACGUGCUGCCUCCGACCGCGCGCCGUAGCCGCCUGGGUGUCCUCUUUUGCCCGCGCCCCGAUGGCACGGCCGACAUGCACAUCAUCAUCAACGGCGAGGACAUGGGCCCGAGCGCCCGGGGACUGCCAGCUGCGCAGCCCCUCUACGCGGUGGUGGACGUGUUUGCUUCCACAAAGAGCGUGCGCCUUGUCCAGCUCGAGUAUGGCUGUAGGUAUCCCUGGGCAGCGACCCCUCCUGGCUCAGUGUGGGGACUGGAAUCUACUAGGGCUCCGUAGCCCAUGUGCUAGGCCUUCGUCUGUCCGGCACUAGUUUAAGAGUGGGAGAAUCUAGCUUCAAAUUGCACCUCUGCUUGUGAUCUUGCACAAGCCUCUACAUGGUUUUGGGCCUUGGUACCUAUCUUGGUUGAUUGAUUAAGAUGCCCUACAAGUUCCCUUUUAGUUUUGAUAGUGUUUCCUGUAUUCACCUAGGGCAGGGAUUCUAAACCAAUUUUAGAUAUUAGGGGCCUCUUUGAGAAUUGUUUGCCCUUUUCUUAGAAACAUGCUUGGCCGGGCACAGUGGCUCACACCUGUAAUCCCAGCACUUUGGGAGGGGGAGGCAGGCAGAUCACUUGAGGCCAGGAGUUCGAGACCAGCCUGGCCAACAUGGUGAAAGCCUGUCUCUACUAAAAAUACAAAAAGUAGCUGGGUGUGGUGGCAUGUGCCAAUAAUCCCAGCUAUUCAGAAGGCUGAGGCAGGAGAGUCACUUGAACCCGAGAGGUGGAGGUUGCAAUGAGCCGAGAUCUCACCAGUGCACUCCAGCCUAGGCAACAGAGCAAGACUCUGAAAAAAAAAAGAAAGAGAGAGAGAGAGGAAGAGAGAGAAAGCAAGCAAGCAAGCAAGCUAGCUAGCUCAAGCCUGGGCAACAAAGUGAGACCCCAUCUGUACAAAAAAUUAAAUAAUUAUCUGGGCAUGGUGGUGCAUGCCUGUAGUCCCAGCUAUUUGGGAGGCUAAGGCAGGAGGAUCGCUUGAGCCCAAGAAUUGAAGGCUGCAGUUCACUGAGCACUGCACUUCAGCCUGGGUGACAGAGCAAGACCCUCUCUCUUUAAAUAAAAAAAAAAAAAGAAAGAAAAGAAAGAAACAUGCUCAUAGACUUGGGCAUAUUGGCUAUUGGCUUCGAGGCAUAACAAACCCCAGACUGAGAGCUUCUUAAUGCUGAGUAUGAUUCAUUAUAGCCCUGGUAAGCAUUGCAGUUAUACCUCUCAUCACAUUUCAUGAACUCAAUGCACCAGAACCCUCUUUGUGCCAGGCCUGUGCUGGAGGCUUCAGUUGCACAGGCAAAUCAGACACUACCCCUGCCCCCAGAAGCUGCUAAGUGAAUGGGGAAGGGAUUGUGCUAAGUGUUAUGAUAUAAACAGGGCUGCAGCUUUGUGGCAGCUCUCAGGAAGAGGUGCUUCUCUCAGCCCCAUGAAGCAGGCUGGGCCCAGAGAGCAGUAAGGACUUGCCCACAUUUAAUGACAAAGUGGGGACCAUGACCUAGACCUUCUGGAUCUUGGCCUCAGACCCACCCUCCAGUUCAGUUUGCCUUUCACAGUCUUCUUCCCACAGUGCCAUCCCUGCAGACUCUGUGCCGCCUAGUGAUACAAAGGAGCAUGGUGCACCGGCUGGCCAUUGAUGGGCUCCACCUGCCCAAAGAACUUAAGGAUUUCUGCAAGUAUGAGUGAAGACCCACAGUGCACCAGAGCACAGCUGCAUCCUGGAGCCCCAGACCUGUGGCUGGCUGGUCCGAAGUUGGCCACAUUGCUGCCAGCCAAGACCAGAAAUAAACAGCCGAUGCUGACAUCUUGAUCACUGGAAGGUCUCCUUGCCCCUACAGCCUAUGAGAGUCACUUCGUUUAGAAUCACUGCAGGUUCUAGAAUGAAUAGGUCAACGCUGUAAAGUGGAUUCCAAGUGUGAAGGGGAGGGUCUAUGAGGUGACAUUCUAGAAGGGUGAAGAAGGGAGGACAGGCGGCAGAUCACUAUUCCCUCACAAACCGGGGCUUUGGGGAAGCCAUGUCCUACUUCAGGACUCCACAAACUCAUCCAGGUCCUCUGCCUUCCGGCCAAGGUGGGGCUGCUUCUCCAGGCUUGUCCCUUGGCCUCUGUAGUCCUGUAGAGCCAGUGGUGGUGGCCUCUGGUGGAACAGGCCCACUGAGCCAGAAAGCUGAGCAGGUGGCACCUGCUGCCCAGGCCUGGGGCCCAGCCCUGGCAAUGCCACAAGCCAGGGGCUGCCCUGGGGGGACUAGCUGGGAGACACUACGGAAGGAAUACAGCCGAAACUGCCACAAAUUCCCGCAUGUGAGGCAGCUGGAGAGCUUGGGCUGGGACAAUGGCUACUCCAGAAGCAGAGCCCCUGACCUGGGUGGCCCCAGCAGGCCUAGGCCCCUGAUGCUGUGUGGGCUGUCACCACGGGUUCUACCGGUACCCUCUGAGGCAGUGGGGAAGGAGGCCAGCUCCCAGCCUGAUAUCUGCAUCCUCACCCUCGCCAUGAUGAUCGCUGGCAUCCCCACCGUGCCCGUCCCAGGAGUUCGGGAAGAGGACCUGAUCUGGGCCGCUCAAGCUUUCAUGAUGGCCCAUCCGGAGCCAGAGGGUGCUGUGGAGGGGGCGCGGUGGGAGCAGGCACAUGCCCACACAGCCUCUGGGAAGAUGCCCCUAGUGAGAUCUAAAAGGGGCCAGCCUCCUGGCUCCUGCUUGUAGAUGGAUGAAAUAGCACCAGAUAUGUA